UCCAGAACUUUAAGAAAUAAAUCUCUGGUCUUUAUAAAUGACCCAGUCUCAGGUAUUCUGUUGUAGCAGCACAAACAAAGACAGGAAGAGCCAGAAUUUUUUUUUUUCCUCUUAAAUCCUAUUAAGCCUCAGAAUCUGCAUACUGCUUUUUGGAACCUGAAUACCACCAAUUGAGUCAUUUUAUGAAAUGUGUCCACUGUCUUAUUCUAACAUAAUGGUCAAAAGAUGUUUAGUUUGCAUGUCAGUCAGCUACUUCCCAAGAAGAUAUUGUUUGACCUGGCUUUUCUACAAGCUCACUGUCCUGUCCUAAUAGCAGGACAGGGAUCCAUGAAAAUAGAAGGAACUGAGCAGAUUUCCCUGAACUUGGUAGGCAUGGGUUAUUACAGCUAGUCUAGCUCUGGCAGGUUCCCCCUGUACAUAGCCAGUAGUUAAGCACCGUAUCAUGAAUCAGGUUUGAAUUAUCGCCUCUAUUCAUAGCACAGAAUAAGUUAAUUUGAGACGGAUAUGUCUUUGUUCAAGGUAGACUUAUUGCCUUAUUUUUUCCUAGUAGAUAUUUACUAAACUCAUAUGUUCUUUCUAGUGCUGCCACGUCUAUACCAUUGCUCCUGAAAUCUUAGUUCAAAUCCAACUUCUGCCACUUUAGCACCUUGUCAUUUUAUCCAUCUAAGCUGAAAUUCAAAGCCUCUAACUCCUACUCUUAGGUGAAGAUUUUUUUUUCCCUGAUCUCUUCUCACAUGUGAGACUUUGUGGGUAUCAGGAGCCAUGGGGACUAGGCAGCCUGGUAAUUACAUUGUUUACUUCCUAGUUUCACACAAAACCAAGUCAAUCCUGGGCCUGCCACCAAGCACCCUUUAGGGAAAUAUAUUUCAAAAAGCUUCACUGAAACCACUUAUUUAUUGACAUUCAGAGACAGUUAAUCAUUCUGCCGAGCAAGAAACACUUAGACCAAACAAGAAACAGCCCAACCUUUCAAGCACCGAGCCUUUGUCAAAGGUUUAUUGAGAAAAGAAAGGCACAAAAGAACCAGCGUUGCCAAACUCGGGCAGCCAUUGUCAACCCUUUGCCAAGUGAUAGUAUCAUAUGGCAUCAGACAUGAGCUUAAGAAAGAGAAAAAAGGAGGAAGGAAUAAGCUUUCUUUCCAUAUAUAAAUCAGAUUGAAGUUACUGUUCCUUUUUGGGACUUUCAGUGUUUAUCCUCUUUCUGGAAUAUAUUUUCCUUCUUCUUGCUUCAGCUCACCAUCCCCAAAACAUACACAUGCACACACAUGCACAUUGUCCCAUACCUUCAUAAUAUAUUUGAAUGAUACAGUCUGCUAAAAUUACUGUCACAGACAUUAUCUUCAUCUUGGACACCUGUUUGUUCUAGUUCCUGGCUGCCUGGAAGUUCUGAAAACGUGACUCAGCCUAGAGCUUUUUGUUAAACCAUAAGGAAAGCUACUAAUUUCUCUACACAGAGAUAGCAUGUAUAAAGUAAUCACCACUGUGAUCCAGAAAUGGUGAUGUCUACACUGGGAGUGAUUGAUGGUGGUUAUUACUGGGGUGGAGAUGGUACGAGUGACAUCUUAAGAUACAUUUAUUAAAAUGGGCCAAGAACCACAUGAAAUGCUUUGCUUGUUUUGAAGUAGGUUUCUUUGCCCAAAGGUUAAGGAAAUAUUUCAAAAAGGCAAAAAGAGAUUGACCCCCACACACUCUCUUAUUUUCUGUAUGAACAUUUUCAAGCUACAGAAAAGUUGAAAGAAUUGUACAUGAACUACACUCACCACCUGAAAUCUACAACUAAAAUUUUUCAUAUUUGCCUGAUCACAUAUGUAACCAUCUAACCAUCCCUCUAUCAAGUAAUGUAUCUUUUUAUUUAACUGUAUUUCAGAGCAAGUUGCAAACAUCAGUUCAUUUCACCCCAGCACUUCAAUAUGCAUUGCAUUAACUGAAGAGAAGUUAAACUUCUAGAGAAACCUAACAGACAAUAUCCACAACAGGUGGUAACAGAAAACAAUCCAGAUGGGGUGCAGGUGCUGUAAAAUAAUACAAAGCUAUCUCUUUGAUCCAGUUCAAGUGCCCUCUCCUGGCUAUGUCAAUGAAGUCAACAGCUGCAAGCUAGAUGAAGACGACACUGAUAAAUUAAAAGGCAAAUGGAGCAGUGAAGUCUUGGUGCAGAAAAAUGACCCUCAGAGGCAGGGCUCAAAGAAGACUGAGAGCAGCAGCAGGACAGCUGAUCCAUGGGAGCCCUGCUGGCCUCACCAAGGGCCGCUCCCACAGGGGGACGCUGGAGGGGAACACCAUGCCUGCGGUGUCAACGGCAUCGGCCCUGCUGCCACUCCACAGCCCACUGGGAAUUCCAGCCCCACCCAGGAUGACAGGGGCUCCUGGGCCAGUACUGCAAAUACUGUUCCCCCAACUCAACCCUUCCUGGAAGGAGGGGGCACCAGGAAACAGGACUGUGUGCUGCUGGCCUCAGAAGGGACCCAAGUCAUGAGAAAUGGAGACUCCAGAGCUCCUUCUGAGGCAGAAAGUUUUGCCUUGGAAGUACAAGACCAUGUCUUCCAGAUACCAGCCCCAGAUUACCUUCAGCAUUGGGGCCCAGCUGGAGACAACGUUGAUCAUAAUGAAAAGGACUGUGUUUUCAAGAACCAUACUGAGGAUGAAUCCCUAGAGGGAAUUCAGCCCCCAGUGGGGGAGCAUGGUUUGAAUACGCCCUUCUCUGUGAGGAGAAGCUGGGAUUCAUUGAAUGAGGAUGUGGAAACAGAAGUUCUAAGCAUCUGCUUUAAUGAGAAGGGUCCUGUUCAUGCCAUGCCUGUGGUUGACUCAGGAAACAGGCAGGAGGAUACCCAUGGCUCCGAUGGAGAUGGGGAUGGGGAGAUUGUGGACGAGGAUGCAGCGGUGGCGGAGGCCCUUGCAGCUUUAGAAGCUGCUACUGCAGGAGAAGAUUUGGAUGAGACUGAUUAGGGGAGGGGAUUUGCACAGGGAGGUAAGCUGGUGUCAUGCUGAGCAUGCAGAUGCAUUUGCUCCCUGGAUGCAUAGCAGGUGAUUCUGCCAGCAUGCACCAGUGCAGCCUUACCAGUUGUUUACAUCCAGCAUCUGUUCUGAUUGUCAGCAUCUGUCCCAUGCUGCUUGUCACAUAUCUGGAGUUUCACUCUGUGUAGAUGAGCUGUCAUUCAGGACACUAGGAGAAAAAUCUGAGUGGGUCAUUGUGCCCAUAUCCACAGAAAAUGCAGAAGUUGAACAGCUUGCUUGACAACCCUCAAACAUCUUUGAGCACCUGGUACAGAUGUUUAUGAGAAUACUCUAAGAUCUCAACCCUUGAUCCCAAAGGCACACAAUCACAGAGCAUUCCUUUUGACUGUAAACUGUUUACCUUGCUUUUGAGAGCCAAACAUUGUACCCAACCUGGAAAAAGUAACUACCCCAAUUAAAGUGCCUCAUGUGUCCCCAGAGCAUGGCUUAACUUCAGGGACAAUCACCCAGGGAACUAAUAACUAACCAGUUGUUCAACAGCGGGUUAAGCUCAGCAGUUUUCACAGUAGAGCAGAAGUCCCCAGGAAACAAAGGGUUAGUCAUUAGCUGAGAUGUUGAUUUUAAAACACCUUGACCUUAACUUUUUUACAUUAUUACUUUUAAAUCUCCUUUGGGAUUGGGGAGGCUGGCCAAAAUAAGUCUUAAAACUGCUUAUGUCAUAUUUGGAUUUUAAGUUCAUGACAUUCGGAACAGCAAAGCCAUAUAUGCAAUGUUUUUAUGCCAUUAAAUGUCUGAUUCCAAUUAAAAUAUAACAACGUAUGUGUCUUUCUAGAAGUCUUAACUCAAAGGUGGUUCUAAUUUUCUCAGAAUAUCAGUGACCCUGGAUGUUACUUUCAAUGUAAAGAACUAAUCUAGAUGGCCGGGCGUGGUGGCUCAUGCCUGUAAUCCCAGCACUUUGGGAGGCCGAGGCGGGUGGAUCACAAGGUCAGGAGUUCAAGAUCAGCCUGGCCAACAUAGUGAAACCCUGUCUCUACUAAAAAUACAAAAAAUUAUCCGGGCACGGUGGCGGGCGCCUGUAAUCCCAGCUACUUGGGAGGCUGAGGCAAGGAGAAUCACUUGAACCUGGGAGGUGGAGGUUGCAGUGAGCUGAGAUCGUGCCACUGCACUCCAGCCUGGGUGACAGUGCAAGACUCCAUCUCAAAAAAAAAAAAAAAAAAAAGAGCUAAGCUAGGCACAGUGGCUCAUGUCUGUAAUCUGAGCACUUUGGAAGGCUGAGGUGAGAGGAUUGCCAGGGCCAGGAAUUCGAGACCAACCUGGGCAAUUUAGCGAGACCCCAUCUCUAUGAAAAAAAAAAAAAAAAAAAGAGCUAGACUACAAAAUUAUACUCAAGGAAGGGACCGAGCUGGUUUGCAGAGCCAUAGCUUUGGCUUUCUCUCUGUCAAACUUGAUGCCAUAACUAAAUGUCCUGAUCUUACCUCAAAGAUGAACAAGCCCUCUCUGGAUUUCAGCCUUCUAAUUCACUGAAACAAGGACAACCAUUCUAACGUAACUCAAUGGAGAAUUUAAAGGCAUUAAGGAUGCUCAAAACUAUCUAGAAAAAAAUAAACAUGGAAGAUGCUUUAGUUUGGUGUUUUGUAACACAGAAUUGAAAUCUGACUGAACUUCAUUUGAUUUCCAGCUUUGCCAUGUGACCUUGGACAAGUUAUGUAUCCCUUUACCCAUCUGUAAAGUGAGAAGAAUAAUUGUAUGUGCUUGUAAAGGUUAAAUGAGAUGAUGUAAGUGUUUAGCACAGUGCUUGGCACACUAGGCACUCAAAAAUGAUGUUUUACUAGUUGAAAACAAUUCCUUUAACAAACAUUUUUACAUCCCCACAACUGAAAACUCUAAAACUGGGAAGUAUGUAUAAUGUCAUUAUUUGACUUUGGCAAUUAUUUAGUAUAAAACAUGAUUUCUGAGCCUUCCAGCACCUUUAAGGACGGCACCCUUACAAAUGCUUAAUGAGCCUAUGGGUUUGUUUGGUACUGUAAUGACAAGCCAUCGCAAGUGACCUCUAUAUACAGGGUCACUCAGAGCCCUUAAAAAGAUAAAGUCUUGGCAUUGUUAAUUGCAUUAGAGGUAUGUCUCCUUUUGUAUUUAGUACACCAAAUACUUAAUAUUUCAGAAUGCUUAUUCCUUCAAUGAUUUCCUAAGUGUAUCAGUUGAGAUUAUGUUCAGUUGUAUGGGACGAGUGUUUUAUACAAAUAGAGGCUUAUUUACCUCUUAUGUAAAAGAAGUCUGGAGUUAGUGAUCCAGGGUGGUAGAGAAUGUAUCACUGGCCCGUGUAUCAAUGACCCACAUAUCAAUGACCCACGUAUCAAUGACCCGCAUAUGAAUGACCCAUGCUGCUUCAAUCAUUUUGGUUUCCUUCUCAAGAUCACUUUGUAGUCCAUAAUGGCUGCUGUGGCUUCAGUCAUUACAUUUGCAUUCCAUGUUGGAAAAAGAAUAAAGGAAUAAAAACCCCA